AGUCGCUCCCCAGCACCCUGUGGGACAGAGCCUGGCGUGUCGCCCAGCGGAGCCCCUGCAGCGCUGCUUGCGGGCGGUUGGCGUGGGUGUAGUGGGCAGCCGCGGCGGCCCGGGGCUGGACGACCCGGCCCCCCGCGUGCCCACCGCCUGGAGGCUUCCAGCUGCCCACCUCCGGCCGGGUUAACUGGAUCAGUGGCGGGGUAAUGGGAAGCCACCCGGGAGAGUGAGGAAAUGAAACUUGGGGCGAGGACCACGGGUGCAGACCCCGUUACCUUCUCCACCCAGGAAAAUGCCCCGCUCCCUAACGUCCCAAACGCGCCAAGUGAUAAACACGAGGAUGGCAAGAGACCCACACACCGGAGGAGCGCCCGCUUGGGGGAGGAGGUGCCGUUUGUUCAUUUUCUGACACUCCCGCCCAAUAUACCCCAAGCACCGAAGGGCCUUCGUUUUAAGACCGCAUUCUCUUUACCCACUACAAGUUGCUUGAAGCCCAGAAUGAUAUACACUUCAGAUAACUACACCGAGGAAAUGGGCUCAGGGGACUAUGACUCCAUGAAGGAACCCUGUUUCCGUGAAGAAAAUGCUAAUUUCAAUAAAAUCUUCCUGCCCACCAUCUACUCCAUCAUCUUCUUAACUGGCAUUGUGGGCAAUGGAUUGGUCAUCCUGGUCAUGGGUUACCAGAAGAAACUGAGAAGCAUGACGGACAAGUACAGGCUGCACCUGUCAGUGGCCGACCUCCUCUUUGUCAUCACGCUUCCCUUCUGGGCAGUUGAUGCCGUGGCAAACUGGUACUUUGGGAACUUCCUAUGCAAGGCAGUCCAUGUCAUCUACACAGUCAACCUCUACAGCAGUGUCCUCAUCCUGGCCUUCAUCAGUCUGGACCGCUACCUGGCCAUCGUCCACGCCACCAACAGUCAGAGGCCAAGGAAGCUGUUGGCUGAAAAGGUGGUCUAUGUUGGCGUCUGGAUCCCUGCCCUCCUGCUGACUAUUCCCGACUUCAUCUUUGCCAACGUCAGUGAGGCAGAUGACAGAUAUAUCUGUGACCGCUUCUACCCCAAUGACUUGUGGGUGGUUGUGUUCCAGUUUCAGCACAUCAUGGUUGGCCUUAUCCUGCCUGGUAUUGUCAUCCUGUCCUGCUAUUGCAUUAUCAUCUCCAAGCUGUCACACUCCAAGGGCCACCAGAAGCGCAAGGCCCUCAAGACCACAGUCAUCCUCAUCCUGGCUUUCUUCGCCUGUUGGCUGCCUUACUACAUUGGGAUCAGCAUCGACUCCUUCAUCCUCCUGGAAAUCAUCAAGCAAGGGUGUGAGUUUGAGAACACUGUGCACAAGUGGAUUUCCAUCACCGAGGCCCUAGCUUUCUUCCACUGUUGUCUGAACCCCAUCCUCUAUGCUUUCCUUGGAGCCAAAUUUAAAACCUCUGCCCAGCACGCACUCACCUCUGUGAGCAGAGGGUCCAGCCUCAAGAUCCUCUCCAAAGGAAAGCGAGGUGGACAUUCAUCUGUUUCCACUGAGUCUGAGUCUUCAAGUUUUCACUCCAGCUAACACAGAUGUAAAAGACUUUUUUUUAUACGAUAAAUAACUUUUUUUUAAGUUACACAUUUUUCAGAUAUAAAAGACUGACCAAUAUUGUACAGUUUUUAUUGCUUGUUGGAUUUUUGUCUUGUGUUUCUUUAGUUUUUGUGAAGUUUAAUUGACUUAUUUAUAUAAAUUUUUUUUGUUUCAUAUUGAUGUGUGUCUAGGCAGGACCUGUGGCCAAGUUCUUAGUUGCUGUAUGUCUCGUGGUAGGACUGUAGAAAAGGGAACUGAACAUUCCAGAGCGUGUAGUGAAUCACGUAAAGCUAGAAAUGAUCCCCAGCUGUUUAUGCAUAGAUAAUCUCUCCAUUCCCGUGGAACGUUUUUCCUGUUCUUAAGACGUGAUUUUGCUGUAGAAGAUGGCACUUAUAACCAAAGCCCAAAGUGGUAUAGAAAUGCUGGUUUUUCAGUUUUCAGGAGUGGGUUGAUUUCAGCACCUACAGUGUACAGUCUUGUAUUAAGUUGUUAAUAAAAGUACAUGUUAAACUUA